AAUCUAUGGCUUCCCUUCCGUUUUCGCGUGGUUCUUUUGCAAGCUCUGGAUUCUCUGGAGUUUGAAUGUUUCCAGUAUUGGAACCCCACCAAGUAGGACUGAUCAGGUCUUACAAUUCUAAAACCAUGACCUGUAACUGGGGAAGACCUUUGAAGUUCUGUCCAACAAAGUAUAUGAAGUUUCAGGAAUUAGUGACAUUCAGGGAUGUGGCCAUAGACUUCUCUCGGCAGGAGUGGGAAUACCUGGACCCUAAUCAGAGGGACUUAUACAGGGAUGUGAUGUUGGAGAACUAUAGAAACCUGGUAUCACUGGGAGGACAUUCCAUUUCUAAACCAGUUGUGGUUGAUUUACUGGAGCGAGGAAAAGAGCCCUGGAUGAUUUUGAGGGAAGAAACACAGUUCACAGAGAUGGGGGUCUCACUGGGUUGCUCAGCUGGUCUCUAACUCCUGGGCUCAAGCAGUCCUCCUGCAUUGGCUUCCCAAAGUGCUGAAAAUACAGAUGGAGUCUUGCUCUGUCGCACAGGCUGGAGUGCAGUGGCCCGAUCUCAGCUCACUGCAACCUCCGCCUCCCAGGUUCAAGCAAUUCUCCUGCCACAGCCUCCAAGUAGCUGGGAUUACAGAUUUGGAUUUACAGUGUGAGAUAAUCAGCUACAUAGAAGUACCCACUUAUGAAACAGAUAUAUCCUCUACACAACUUCAGAGCAUAUAUAAGAGAGAGAAACUCUAUGAAUGUAAGAAAUGUCAGAAGAAAUUUAGUAGUGGUUAUCAACUUAUUCUACAUCACAGGUUUCAUGUCAUUGAGAGACCCUAUGAAUGCAAAGAGUGUGGGAAGAACUUUCGUAGUGGCUAUCAACUUACUCUACAUCAAAGAUUUCAUACUGGUGAGAAACCCUAUGAAUGUACAGAAUGUGGGAAGAACUUUAGAAGUGGUUAUCAGCUGACUGUGCAUCAGAGAUUUCAUACUGGUGAGAAAACCUAUGAAUGUAGGCAGUGUGGGAAGGCCUUUAUAUAUGCCUCACACAUUGUUCAACAUGAGAGAAUUCACACUGGUGGGAAGCCGUAUGAAUGUCAGGAGUGUGGGAGGGCCUUUAGUCAAGGUGGACAUCUUAGAAUUCAUCAGAGAGUUCAUACUGGCGAAAAACCAUAUAAAUGUAAGGAAUGUGGGAAGACUUUUAGUAGGCGCUCAAAUCUUGUUGAACAUGGGCAGUUUCAUACUGAUGAGAAGCCAUACAUAUGUGAGAAAUGUGGAAAGGCCUUUAGAAGAGGUCACCAGCUUACUGUACAUCAGAGAGUUCACACUGGUAAAAAGCCAUAUGAGUGUAAAGAAUGUGGGAAGGGCUAUACCACUGCCUCAUACUUUCUUCUACAUCAGAGAAUUCAUAAAGGUGGAAAACCCUAUGAAUGUAAGGAGUGUAAGAAAACCUUUACUUUGUAUAGAAAUCUUACUCGGCAUCAGAAUAUUCAUACUGGUGAGAAACUUUUUGAAUGCAAGCAAUGUGGGAAGACCUAUACUACUGGUUCAAAACUCUUUCAACAUCAGAAAACUCAUACUGGCGAGAAACCCUAUGAAUGCAAGGAAUGCGGAAAGGCCUUUAGCUUGUAUGGCUACCUUAAACAACAUCAGAAAAUUCAUACUGGCAUGAAACACUUUGAAUGUAAGGAGUGUAAAAAAACCUUUACUUUGUAUAGAAAUCUUACUCGACAUCAGAAUAUUCACACUGGUAAGAAACUUUUUGAAUGUCAGGAAUGUGGGAAGGCCUAUAGUACUGGCUCAAACCUUAUUCAACAUCGGAAAACUCAUACUGGUGAGAAACCCUAUAAAUGUAAGGAAUGUGGCAAGACCUUUAGCUUGCAUGGAUAUCUUAAUCAACAUCAGAAAAUUCAUACUGGUAUGAAACCCUAUGAAUGUAAGGUAUGUAGAAAAACCUUUACUUUCUAUAGAAAUCUUACUCUACAUCAAAGUAUUCAUACUGAUGAGAAACCUUUUGAAUGUAAGGAAUGUGGGAAGACCUUUAGACGUAGUUCACACCUUACUGCACAUCAGAGCAUUCAUGCUGAUAAAAAACCCUAUGAAUGUAAAGAAUGUGGAAAGGCCUUUAAAAUGUAUGGCUACCUUACCCAACAUCAGAAAAUUCAUACUGGUGGAAAACCUUAUGAAUGUAAAGAAUGUGGGAAGGCCUUCAGUCGUGCUUCAAACCUUGUUCAACAUGAGAGAAUUCAUACUGGUGAGAAACCCUAUGUGUGUAAGCAGUGUGGGAAAACCUUCAGAUAUGGUUCAGCCCUUAAAGCCCAUCAGAGAAUUCAUAGGAGCAUAAAAGUGUAAGACCGUAAAGAGUACGAGCGCGCCAUUCAUCAUCAGACAGCCCACACUGGUGAGAAAUGAUGGAAUGUUAGUCUUAUAGGUAUGGCUUUAGCAAUUGAGAGAGUUCAAAAUGCAGAUCUUGCCACAUUAGAAAGCAUUCAAUGUCAGUCCUGUUUUAAUGGAAUAUCUGACUAUUCAAUGGUAAAUUAAG